CCUCCAGACUGCAUCAUCUGCAUGGAGAAGCUGUCCACAGCGUCUGGAUACAGCGAUGUGACUGACAGCAAGGCAAUCGGGUCCCUAGCUGUGGGCCACCUCACCAAGUGCAGCCAUGCCUUCCACCUGCUGUGCCUCCUGGCCAUGUACUGCAACGGCAAUAAGGAUGGAAGUCUGCAGUGUCCCUCCUGCAAAACCAUCUAUGGAGAGAAGACGGGGACCCAGCCCCAGGGAAAGAUGGAGGUAUUACGGUUCCAGAUGUCGCUCCCCGGCCACGAGGACUGCGGGACCAUCCUCAUAGUUUACAGCAUUCCCCAUGGUAUCCAGGGCCCUGAGCACCCCAAUCCCGGAAAGCCGUUCACUGCCAGAGGGUUUCCCCGCCAGUGCUACCUUCCAGACAACGCCCAGGGCCGCAAGGUCCUAGAGCUCCUGAAGGUGGCCUGGAAGAGGCGGCUCAUCUUCACAGUGGGCACGUCCAGCACCACGGGUGAGACGGACACCGUGGUAUGGAACGAGAUCCACCACAAGACAGAGAUGGACCGCAACAUUACGGGCCACGGCUAUCCCGACCCCAACUACCUGCAGAACGUGCUGGCUGAGCUGGCUGCCCAGGGGGUGACCGAGGACUGCCUGGAGCAGCAGUGACCUCGCACCCCAGCACGCCCGCCUCUGGUGGCCACCCCGCUGCCCCAUGGCUGGCUGGGUGGCCAGGCAGGAAGUGCCCAGCCCGAGAGGCUGGGAGGUUUGUUGAGGGUGUGGGGUGUGCCCCACCUGAAGCCGGGGCUCCCCCUGCCUGCCUCUCUCUCCUCCUCCCCUCUGGGAAUUGGGCAGCCCUGGGCAGUUGUACUCAUGGGGGCUUAGGAUGCAGCUACCUCAGUGCGCAGGGCCCGUCUGUCCUCUGGGGGCUGCUUCGGGCCCGCGGUGCUCGGGGCCUGGUGUGGGGCGAGUAGAGACUUCCCCAGCCUGGACGGGCGUGGGUUCUGGGUCAGCUUCUUUUACCUCAAUUUUGUUUGCAAUAAAUGCUCUAUAGCCAAA